AGACCGCGGUGACGUCUCCACCGCGCCAAACUCACUGAAAAUCAAACCGCUACCAUUAGGAGCCCUCCACGCUUAACAUAUCCGUUCUUUCUCGUUUGAAAGUAACCAGGCUGCUCCUCCCCAUUUUUCGCCUUCUUCUCGCGGAGGCUGAGAGACUAACCUUACACAACAUGGCGGCCUGGUGUGUCUGGUGUCCUAGAGCGGACGAAAGCAGGUGACUCUCUAGUCAACUUCCGACUUGGACUCCGAAGAUCGCUACAGAAAGAUCUAGAAGAGGUAAAGGUGUUGCUGGAAAAGGCUACUAGGAAAAGAGUACGUGAUGCCCUUACAGCUGAAAAAUCCAAGAUUGAGACAGAAAUCAAGAACAAGAUGCAACAGAAAUCACAGAAGAAAGCAGAACUUCUUGAUAAUGAAAAACCAGCUGCUGUGGUUGCUCCCAUUACAACGGGCUAUACGGUGAAAAUCAGUAAUUAUGGAUGGGAUCAGUCAGAUAAGUUUGUGAAAAUCUACAUUACCUUAACUGGAGUUCAUCAAGUUCCCACUGAGAAUGUGCAGGUGCAUUUCACAGAGAGGUCAUUUGAUCUUUUGGUAAAGAAUCUAAAUGGGAAGAGUUACUCCAUGAUUGUGAACAAUCUCUUGAAACCCAUCUCUGUGGAAGGCAGUUCAAAAAAAGUCAAGACUGAUACAGUUCUUAUAUUGUGUAGAAAGAAAGUGGAAAACACAAGGUGGGAUUACCUGACCCAGGUUGAAAAGGAGUGCAAAGAAAAAGAGAAGCCCUCCUAUGACACUGAAACAGAUCCUAGUGAGGGAUUGAUGAAUGUUCUAAAGAAAAUUUAUGAAGAUGGAGACGAUGAUAUGAAGCGAACCAUUAAUAAAGCCUGGGUGGAAUCAAGAGAGAAGCAAGCCAAAGGAGACACGGAAUUUUGAGACUUUAAAGUCGUUUUGGGAACUGUGAUGUGAUGUGGAAAUACUGAUGUUUCCAGUAAGGGAAUAUUGGUGAGCUGCAUAUAUAAAUUUGACAGAUAGCUAUUUACAUAGCCUUCUAAGUAAAGGCAAUGAAUUCUCCAUUUCCUACUGGAGGAUUUAUUUAAAUAAAAUAUGCUUAUUAAACACUCCUGCAAAGAUGGUUUUAUUAGUACCCUGGUCAUUUUGUUCAAGGAAGGGUUAUAUUGCAUUCUCACGUGAAAUAUAAAAAGCAAGUCUUGCCCAAUAAAAACGCUACAUUGUGUGUAUUUUUUGUUCAGCUAAGAAUUGGAAAAGUAUUUGCUUGCCUUUUAAGUUACUGACAUCAGCUUCCACCAGUGUAAAAAUUGAGUAAAACCUGAAGUUUUGCAUAAAAUGCAAAUCGGUGCCUGUGCUUGAAGGUUGCUGUAGAGCAUCUGACCCCUUAUUACCACCUUAAGCAAUGUAUAUGCCAUGCAUUACCAUGCACUAAUUCAAUCACAGGUGUUUCUAUCUAGAUUUAAAUAUAUUUGUCAAUGAAUGUGGAAUAGAAAAUCUAAACAUGACAAUAAUAGACAUAUCUUUGUAUGGUACCAGUUAGUUUUGCCGUGGAUCAGAUGGUUUAUAAAAGUAAUAACCAUAAAGCAAAAAAUAAUUUGAAAGCCCGUCUAUUCCUAUGCUCAAUAAAGUUAAGUUUUUCUUCAUUAGAACAGUUUUAUGAUUUAUUUGUCUAGGAGUAUGUCAGAAAAAUCAGGCUUUUAGUAGGAAUUACUCCUAUUCCCCCUGAAGUCAGGACCAGUGCCUGUGAUCUCCAUUACUUUAUUUUCCUGGAGGUAUUAGCCAACACAGUUAGAUCAGAGAAAGCAAUUGAAGCCAGGCAUGAAGGCUGGCGCCCGUAAUCCCAGCUACUAAGGCUGGAGGAUCACUUCAGCCCAGGAGUUUAAGGCUGCAGUGAGCUAUGAUGAUGCCACUGUACUGCAGCUUGGGUAACAGAUUGAGAACCUGUCUCAUUAAAAAAAAAAAAAAAAAAAAAGCCGUUAGACACACAGGAAAAAUCCAGAAGGGUAAACUAAACUAAAGCUACAAUUAAUAUGGGAAUUUGGAAGAAGUGGUAGGAUUUAAAAUACAGAAACAGUUUAUGUAUAGGAUAGCUAUAAGUAAAUACUGAAACACAUUAUGCCUCUGUAAUUGGGGUUGACACAUGAACAGAAUAGCAGACACAAUGCAUAUGAAAGUUACAGAAUAUGGUAAAAGUGGGGUAAAGAUGGGUUUUUAAUGAUACUAAGAUAACUGAAAAUAGGCAUAUAGAUAUAUUCCAAGCCGCCUGACGAUCUAAUUGUAAAAAGUAAAGCAUACAAAUACUAGAAGAAAAUGGAGGAAAACGACAUUAUAUGUGACUUAAAACCUAGAAGAAAUAAAUAAAACUAUUGAUCAAUUUUAACUACAUAAAAAUGUUUAUAGGACAAGAAAAACCCCACCAUAACCCAAGGCAAACAAUGUAUUGACAGGAUUCCAAUAAUUAAGAAUACUUCAUACAAAAAGAAAUGUAAAUGACCUUUAACAUGUAAAGAUGCUCACCUUGUUCAGAAGAGAAUAAACCAGUGUUUUUACCUUUCACUUGAAAAAGAAGUAUAAAAACAACUGUAUUGAGUUGAGGCUGUGGAGAAAUAAGGACACAUAUAUGGGAAUGGAAUGCAAAAGUUAAACUUUGGUUAACAAGAAUAUUUGGGCAGGUGCAGUGGCUCACACCUGUAAUCCCAACACCUUGGGAGGCCAAGGUGGGCGGAUCACUUGAGGUCAGGAGUUCAAGACCAUCUGGCCAACAUGGUGAAACCCUGUCUCUACUGAAAAUAAAAAAAACUAGCUGGGCAUGGUGGCAGAUGCCUGUAACUCCAGCUACUCGGGAGACUGAAGGACAAGAAUCACUUGAACC